CCUUCCUCUAUUUUUUCUCUGCAUUUACUCCUCCUCUGAGCAUCUUCGACCCGCAGGGCUACCUGGCUGCUAAUAGCGUAGACGUGGCGGGCCUGGGGGUUCCUGUUCGCCUAGCUCACAGCGCCACGCCGACUACACAGCACCGAAGGGCCCCGAAGGCAACCCGGAAGUUUUGGAGAAAAGGAAAUGACACUCCCUUCAUACCUGGGAAGACGAACCACUUGCCCGAUGUGCACAAAGGGCCAAAAGCCAAAAUGAAACUGAUGGUACUUGUUUUCACCAUUGGGCUAACUUUGCUGCUAGGAGUUCAAGCCAUGCCUGCAAAUCGCCUCUCUUGCUACAGAAAGAUACUAAAAGAUCACAACUGUCACAACCUUCCGGAAGGAGUAGCUGACCUGACACAGAUUGAUGUCAAUGUCCAGGAUCAUUUCUGGGAUGGGAAGGGAUGUGAGAUGAUCUGUUACUGCAACUUCAGCGAAUUGCUCUGCUGCCCAAAAGACGUUUUCUUUGGACCAAAGAUCUCUUUCGUGAUUCCUUGCAACAAUCAAUGAGAAUCUUCAUGUAUUCUGGAGAACACCAUUCCUGAUUUCCCACAAACUGCACUACAUCAGUAUAACUGCAUUUCUAGUUUCUAUAUAGUGCAAUAGAGCAUAGAUUCUAUAAAUUCUUACUUGUCUAAGACAAGUAAAUCUGUGUUAAACAAGUAGUAAUAAAAGUUAAUUCAAUCUAAUUUUUCUCUGUGGACAUUGUUGGCAUUGGUUAAAAAUUUUGCCUAGAAAAUGUAAUCUAUGAGGUGUUCAUUAUACUCAGUUAAAGAGUUCUGUCCCCCAGAUGAAGAGCCAUAGGCAUGGCUCAAGGAUUGAAAAUACUUUCAGUCCUUAGUUGACAGUUAUUAACCACAUAUUGAAAGAACCAGGUAUAAGCUGAGAUUCUUGGAAGGGAGCUAGAAAUUUUCUAGUAAGAAGGAAAAAGGGACCAGCCUGGGCAACAUAGUGAGACCCCCUCUUUACAAAAAAAUUAAAAAAUUAGCAGGUUGUGGGUGCCCACAUCUGUAGUUCUAGUUACUCAAGAGGGUCAUUUGAAUCUAGAAUUUCGAGUCUGCAGUGAGCUAUGAUUGCACUACUGCACUCUAGCCUGGGUGACAGAGCAAGACCCUGUCUCGAAAAAAAAAAAAAAAAAAAAAAAAGGAAAAGGGAACAAUAUUUGAGGGUAUAUUAUGUAUGCUAAUAACUUUAAGUACAUUUCAGGCUGGGACUGGUGACUAAUGCCUGUAAUCCUAGCAUUUUGGGAGGCCAAGGCGGGAAGAUCACUUGAGUCCAGGAGUUUGAGACCAGCCUGGGCAACAUAGUGAGAUCCUGUCUUUACAAAAAAAAUUUAAAAAUUAGCUGCAUGGCGGCAUGCACCUGUAGUCCCAGCUAUUUGGGAGGCUGAGGUAGGAGGAUCACUCGAGCCCAGAAAUUCAAGGCUGCAGUGAGCUAAGAUGAUGCCACUGAACUCCACCAUGGAACCACAGAGUGAGACUCUGUCUCAAACAAACAAACAAAAACCAAGAACUUUAAGCACAUUUCAUUUUACUCUCUUAAAAAACAACAACAAAAGCCUUCAAGGUAAAUAUUCUCAGCCCCAUUUUUCAGCUGCUAACUCAAGUUUAAGAUAUUUGCUAAAAAUCAAGGCAGAUUUUCAAGAGUUCCAAUUCCAAAGCCCAUAUGCCACACACAGAUGUAUCCUUAAAACCAUGAUACAUUUCCUAAAGUAUCCAUUUUUAAGAAUAACAAAACACACAUUAAAAGAAACAUAAUGGAUGAGAAUUUAAAAGUAUCAUACAUUUUAAAAGUAAAUAAAACAGGGAACUUCAAAGGUAUUUUCUGAUUGUUAGAGGAGACAGCUUUGGAUUAUGCCCCAUAACUUAAGAGGUAUGUGACUCAUAUUGCCAUCAGAGGUAAUGUCAGAAAGUCUUUCAUGUUAUAAAAAUGUAUUCAAAGCCUGCUAAGUGCCAGCCAUUAUUAAGAUCUGGGCAUACAGUAAUGAAUAAAAUGGACUUAUCUUCUUGGAACUUGUGCUCUAACAAAGGUGUGAUUGCUAUAAACAAGUAAUUAUUUAUAAAUGUGAAGCCUGCUACAGAGAAGUAUAGGGUGCCAUACAAAGUAUUGUGGGGAAAUGUUUGAGAGACACCAUACCACACAGGCAAUCUGGGAGAUAUCAUUUUAUGAAUAAAAGUGACAUUAUUUCAUUAAAAUAUAUCCUUGGAGGUCCCUGAUCUGUUUCUGGAGACCACACCCAGAACAGUAUCUGGUAUCUAAUCUGUGUUUAGUAAGUGUUACUGGGCUGAAAGACCACACCCAAAACAGUGUCUGGUAUCUAAUCUGUGUAAAUAAGUGUUACUGGGCUGGACCAAACAAUUUUGAGGUAGUCACAAUUCAGUGUCUUAAAGUGUAUAUAAACACGGCUGGGUGCGGUGGCUCACGCCUGUAAUCCCAGCACUUUGGGAGGCGGAGGCGGGCUUAUCACGAGGUCAGGAGAUCAAGACCAUCCUGGCUAAUACGGUGAAACCUCGUCUCUACUAAAAAUACAAAAAAAAAAAAAAAAAAAAUUAGCUGGGCGUGGUGGCAGGCGCCUCUAGUCCCAGCUAUUUGGGAGGCUGAGGCAGGAGAAUGGCGUGAACCCAGGAGGUGGAGCUUGCAGUGAGCUGAGAUCGUGCCACUGCACUCCAGCCUGGGCGACAGAGUGAGACUCCGUCCCCCCAAAAAAAAAGUGUAUAUAAACACAAGUCAGAACAUGUUUUCGAACAGUGUAAGCUCCUAUAAAAUACAUGAAGUGAAAUUGUAAAAUAAUAUAGAUAGGUAGGUAGAUGGAUAAUAUUAGUUGUUUUAUCAAGAUAGCAUGUGAUUUGAUUGGCCUUUCUUUCUUCACUGAAUUGACUGGUAAUGAAAUCAGCCUAACUCAAUAAUGAAAGUUUCAUAUCCAUUCUGGAACAAUGCAUAGAAUAGGUAAAUUUAAAAAAACUAUCAGCAAACCAGUUUUAUUUUCUACUUGGUAGGAACUCUCCUUGAGGGGGAAAAAGCAUUAAAGAUCCAGUGUCUCCAUUUACAAAUGACACAUCAGCAUAAGGACAUAUGUGAGACAACAACGGCUUUUUAGUAAACGUUCCCUUACUACUGCAAUCAAAGCCUGGUAAGAAAAAUUGUAUCUAACAAAGCUAAAUAUUUAAUAAAUAAAAUUUUAUAAAUUAUUCAUCAUAAUGUCUUUCUGAAAAUAUGAAAUUCAGUUAUUUCUUUUAGAAAUGAAUGCAUUAUACAAGUACACAGCCUUCUUUAUAUUACAAAAUAAAUGUAAAAACAUACAUUCACACAACUUACCUUAUAUAACUAUUUCUCUAACUUGGUCAAUGCAUUUUUAAAAACAAUAGAUUUUUUUUUUUUUUUGAAACUGAGUCUCACUCUGUCACCCAGGCCAGAGUACAGUGGCACAAUCUUGACUCACUGCAACCUCUGCCUCCCAGGUUCAAGUGAUACUUGUGCUUCAACCUCCUGAGUAGCUGGGACUACAGGCACUUGUCACCAUGCUCAGCUAAUUUUUGUAUUUUUUAGUAGAAAUGAGGUUUUGCCAUGUUGGACAGGCUGGUCUCCAACUCCUGGCCUCAAAUGAUCUGCCUGCCUUGGCCUCCCAAAGUGUUAGGAUUACAGGCAUGAGUUUUUCCAAUAGAUUUUAGUUAUAAGACAACUAAGCUUUUAUUAAAAUUUUAUUAUUCUUCUAAACACCAUCUUGCAGCAACUGAAUGAGAUAGGUACUGAUAUUAUCCUUGUUCUAUGGACAAAAAAGCUAAGGUUUAAAGAUAUUAAGUAGUUUGUCUAAGUUUACAUUAUCAGUGAGCAAUUGAGCCAGAUUUUGAAUAUGGCCAGUCUUACACUAGCAUCUAGAGUCUUAACCACUAUGUUGUUUAACAGCAUUACCUAAUGCAUUAUUUCCUUUACAGAAAGGCAAACUUUUACAUGGAUAGGACACACAAUUGUACAUUUCAGAUAGCUCAUAUAUGCUAAAAGCUUACUGAACAAGUAUUUCUGUAUUGUUAUCUUUGACUUUCUAUAUCAUUGUUCUUACUGUGAAUCCCACGUUACUGAGCACAAAGUUGACAGUAAUACAUAUUAAUAGCUCACCUCUUUUUAAUUAAAAUUCAUCUUUUCUUCAUCGUAA